UCGCUCUCACACACACACAAGUGCACAUAAGUGUGUAUGCUUCCUCUCCCACUCUCUCACAAACAUACACAGACUCACACCCUUCCCACAAUGCAGCAAAGCCAUCUGGAGCCCCAGCCAGUGUGUGAUGCGUUUUGCCUCUGUCUGGACUUCUGCACUUCCUGGCUUCACCCAACCUGAAACUGCUGGGUGCAGCCCGAGCACCAGUGACAGCCCUGGUUGUCCCAUGGCCUCUUGAGGAACCCAGGUCUCCAGUCAAAGCCACUGGAGUAGGGGGACCCAUAGAGACCUGAGGUACUCAUGAGACCCAUGGAAAAUCAUCUGCACACACACUGCUAAGGAGUCAAAGGACAGAAGUGAUGGGGCUGGUAAGUAGCAAAAAGCCGGACAAGGAAAAGCCGAUCAAAGAGAAGGACAAGGGCCAAUGGAGCCCCCUGAAGGUCAGCGCCCAAGACAAGGACGCCCCGCCACUGCCGCCCCUGGUUGUCUUCAACCACCUUACUCCUCCACCGCCCGAUGAACACCUGGAUGAAGACAAGCAUUUCGUGGUGGCUCUGUAUGACUACACCGCUAUGAAUGAUCGGGACCUGCAGAUGCUGAAGGGGGAGAAGCUACAGGUCCUGAAGGGAACUGGAGACUGGUGGCUGGCCAGGUCACUCGUCACAGGAAGAGAAGGCUAUGUGCCCAGCAACUUUGUGGCCCGAGUGGAGAGCCUGGAAAUGGAAAGGUGGUUCUUUAGAUCACAGGGUCGGAAGGAGGCUGAGAGGCAGCUUCUUGCUCCAAUCAACAAGGCCGGCUCCUUUCUUAUCAGAGAGAGUGAAACCAACAAAGGUGCCUUCUCCCUGUCUGUGAAGGAUGUCACCACCCAGGGGGAGCUGAUCAAGCACUAUAAGAUCCGCUGCCUGGAUGAAGGGGGCUACUACAUCUCCCCCCGGAUCACCUUCCCCUCGCUCCAGGCCCUGGUGCAGCACUAUUCUAAGAAGGGGGAUGGUCUAUGCCAGAGGCUGACCCUGCCCUGUGUGCGCCCGGCCCCGCAGAAUCCCUGGGCCCAGGAUGAAUGGGAGAUCCCCCGGCAGUCUCUCAGGCUGGUCAGGAAACUCGGGUCUGGACAAUUCGGCGAAGUCUGGAUGGGUUACUACAAAAACAACAUGAAGGUGGCCAUUAAGACGCUGAAGGAGGGAACCAUGUCUCCAGAAGCCUUCCUGGGUGAGGCCAACGUGAUGAAGGCUCUGCAGCACGAGCGGCUGGUCCGACUCUACGCAGUGGUCACCAAGGAGCCCAUCUACAUUGUCACCGAGUACAUGGCCAGAGGAUGCCUGCUGGAUUUCCUGAAGACAGAUGAAGGGAGCAGAUUGUCACUCCCAAGGCUGAUUGACAUGUCGGCGCAGAUUGCUGAAGGGAUGGCAUACAUUGAGCGCAUGAAUUCCAUCCACCGCGACCUGCGGGCGGCCAACAUCCUGGUGUCUGAGGCCUUGUGCUGCAAAAUUGCUGAUUUUGGCUUGGCUCGAAUCAUCGACAGUGAAUACACGGCCCAAGAGGGGGCCAAGUUCCCCAUCAAGUGGACAGCCCCGGAAGCCAUCCACUUCGGGGUCUUCACCAUCAAAGCAGACGUGUGGUCGUUUGGAGUCCUCCUGAUGGAAGUUGUCACUUAUGGGCGGGUGCCAUACCCAGGGAUGAGCAACCCCGAGGUCAUCCGCAACCUGGAGCGCGGCUACCGCAUGCCGCGCCCCGACACCUGCCCGCCCGAGCUGUACCGCGGCGUCAUCGCCGAGUGCUGGCGCAGCCGGCCCGAGGAGCGGCCCACCUUCGAGUUCCUGCAGUCGGUGCUGGAGGACUUCUACACGGCCACCGAGCGGCAGUACGAGCUGCAGCCCUAGCCGGCCGCGCCCGCCUGCGCCCCGUGCCCACCUCUGCGCGGACGACCCCGACUUCCGUGCCAUCCCAGACGGGCCGCGAAGGCGGGGUGUCGCCUGUGCCCUUUUCUCAGACCCGGAAUCCAGUGGGCAGAGGCAGCUUCGCAGGGGGUCCCCGGACGGACUCCUUCACCGACUGCACCCCCGGGCGAGUUACGCGGCCUCUCUGUGCCGCUUCAUUUGUAGAGGGCUGUAACAGUGACCUCGCACGGUCAUCCGGAGUACUAAGCCCCAGUAAGGUGUUCAGGACUGGUAAGCGACUGUCAUCAAGUAAGGCCCCCGUGCUGGGCACCCCCCGUGCUGGCCGCGUCCCCGCCUCUGCGCCCUGCGUGGACCCCGCCCUGCCCCGCUACAGAAGCCAGACUGGGUCCCGCGGACGCCAGCAGGGGCAACCCCAGCCUAGGCUGCGCUCCAGCACUGCGGGGCUUUUCUGCAAUAAAGUCACGAGCGUUCGA